CCGUUUCCGGUCCGGUGGGUACAAGAUGACGGAGCCGGGCGCCUCUCCCGAGGACCCUUGGGUCAAGGCAAGCCCCGUGGGCGCGCACGCCGGCGAGGGGAGGGCGGGUCGGGCUCGUGCACGUAGGGGGGCCGGAAGACGAGGGGCUUCCCUCCUGUCCCCAAAGUCCCCCACGCUCUCCGUGCCCCGGGGCUGCAGAGAAGACAGCUCUCACCCCGCGUGUGCCAAGGUGGAGUAUGCCUACAGCGACAACAGCCUGGACCCCGGGCUUUUUGUAGAAAGCACCCGCAAGGGGAGUGUAGUGUCCAGAGCUAAUAGCAUCGGUUCCACCAGUGCCUCUUCUGUCCCCAACACAGAUGAUGAGGACAGUGAUUACCACCAGGAGGCCUACAAGGAGUCCUACAAAGACCGGCGGCGGCGCGCACACACUCAGGCUGAGCAGAAGAGGAGGGACGCCAUCAAGAGAGGCUAUGAUGACCUUCAGACCAUCGUCCCCACUUGCCAGCAGCAGGACUUCUCCAUUGGCUCCCAAAAGCUCAGCAAAGCCAUCGUUCUACAAAAGACCAUUGACUACAUUCAGUUUUUGCACAAGGAGAAGAAAAAGCAGGAGGAGGAGGUGUCCACGUUACGCAAGGAUGUCACCGCCCUAAAGAUCAUGAAAGUGAACUAUGAGCAGAUUGUGAAGGCACACCAGGACAACCCCCAUGAAGGGGAGGACCAGGUCUCUGACCAGGUCAAGUUCAACGUGUUUCAAGGCAUCAUGGAUUCCCUGUUCCAGUCCUUCAAUGCCUCCAUCUCAGUGGCCAGCUUCCAGGAGCUGUCAGCGUGUGUCUUCAGCUGGAUCGAGGAGCACUGUAAGCCUCAGACCCUGCGGGAGAUUGUGAUUGGCGUCCUGCACCAAUUGAAAAACCAGCUUUACUGACCGGUUCUUGGAAACCUGGAGAACAGCCAACAAGAGGCCCUUGAAUCUCUACGUGGCCACUGAACUGCUGGGCCCGGGAGACUGGACUACAACACCUCACACUGGUCAGCUGGUUUCUACUUGGUGUUUGGUUUUUCCCAGCCCCAUUUUAUCUUCAGCGGAGCCGCGGUGUUUGUUUUGUGAAAGCUUCUGAUUAAUUUAUUAUAUUGACGAUAAAACUCAAACCUACCCAGCCUUCCCCCCACUCCAUGGAAGUCCUUGGGAUGGGCGUCUGCUCUGGACACCCCAAAGAGCUCCUGCCCUCUCAGCCCUUUAUUCAAGCCUCAGAUUUCUGCUCAUGAUCUACAUAGAUUUGGAAACUGUUUUCCUCUGUUUUGGUCUCUUGGGCAACAUUUUUGGCCCAAGUUUGGGCAACAUUUGGCCCAAGUUUGGGCAUUUUGGCAGUAGCUGUAUGGGAGAAAAAGAGUAAGAGGAAAUAUUCCCACAGCCAUGAAGGGUGAAAGGGCACCUUGUGCCUAGACUAGGGCUGCCUGGUCAGUCCCAGGUGAGGCCAAGGGCUUUCUGGCCAUCUCAGGGAGGGGCCACCAGGUUCCUCCCCUCACCCCAUAUUCCAUCACCUUCCUCCUCUGCUCUGGGUGGUAAGGGAAGCCCUCCCGGUUCCCACAGGCUAUGAUGCUGCAUGGCAGAGGCAGGUAUAACACAGCACUACAUAUUGGAAAUUUUUUAUUUUUCUAAAUACCAAUGCAGUUUUGCUACGGUUACAAUUUUGAAAUAUUAACUGAGCCUCAAAAUCACCCUUUCUGUCAAGCAUAUCUUGGCCUCUCCCAUGUCUCAGUGUUGCCUGCAUUUCUCCCAGGACUUGGGGGUGGGGUGAAAAGCGUACAAAAGAUACUUAAAAGGGCUCCUGGGGUACACAAGCCCAGCAGGUCCUGAGUGAAGCCGUGGGCCCUCCAAAUGCUCGUUUUAUAGCAACCUCUCUCUACCCUAGUUCUCCAAAUUCACUUCUGCCUUCCUCAGGUUUGAUAUCUGGCAGGUUUGACUAUCCAGAGGAAAUUAAAUAUUUUUAUAUAAAAUUAAAUUAUAAUAAAUAUUGCCAAAUGCUUUCCUUUAGCAUUGUUCCAAGUCUAAAUGUUAACCUCAAGCUACUGCAAUUUAGACAAUGAAAUGGGCUGGGUCUACCCCCAGCCACCAGCCCUCAUCCUCUCUACCCAGUGCUCUGGUUUAUGCUUGUCUCCUGACUGCUCUGCUUAAAGGUGAAAGUAGCAGGAACAACAACAAAAGCCAACCAAAAACAAGGUAGCCAGUGCAAGACAUCUCACUCUUCUGACAUCCUGCAGUCCCCACCAGUCCUGACCGUGGGCCCCUCAGGGGUCUGGGAGUGUGACGUUGUAAUCUUCAUCCGUCUCUAUCCCAACUUCCUCCUGUGAGACAGGGAGACAAGUGAAUGAGAUGUCACCAGGAUAAGACCACAGGGAAGCAAAGAAGGAAGAGAGCUCCACUUACAAAGAACUGCUUCUUGCUCUUGGGGUAUCCUUCAAGUAUUGCAUCAGACAGCUCUGUAGCCUGACAAGAAAUAAAACCACCCGUUUUCAGAUGGGCA